AGCGCCGCCUGGCCUGGGCCGGACCCGGUCAGGGUUCUCAAGCUGUCGUCCCUAUGGGGCUGUGUUUUCCUUGUCCCGGGGAGUCCGCGCCUCCCACGCCGGACCUGGAAGAGAAAAGAGCAAAGCUUGCAGAGGCUGCAGAGAGAAGACAAAAAGAGGCUGCAUCUCGGGGAAUUUUAGAUGUUCAAUCUGUGCAAGAAAAGAGAAAGAAAAAGGAAAAAAUAGAAAAACAAAUUGCUACAUCCGGGCCCCCACCAGAAGGUGGACUUAGGUGGACAGUUUCAUAAAGCAUAACAUGAGUAGAAGAAUCUACUGCCAAUAACUGUUUAUUAUCUGCAAUCAAGUGGGCUUCAUCAAUUUAAUUUCUUCUCUUUGAGUAAAUGAAGAUUCAGACUUUGUAAUAUUAUUGCCCUUAAGUGCAAUGCUAAAAAAACGUUGAUUUUCAAGCUUAGAGAAUGGCUAGACUUUUCAUUAAAUACUGAUUUUCCUACAUUUGCUCUUCUGCAGUUAGUGGGUGAUUUGCUAUUUUUCUUAGUAGUUAAAAAAUGGAACUAAAUAGUGAAUAUACAUACACUGCAUGUAAACAUUCUGCAUAUACCUCUAAGAUUAAAAUUCGCAGUUGUCUUUUCAUCCUUUAUAAAAUGAUCUAACUACUUAUAUUUGUGCUGCAUCGCGUUACAUCUGUUUUUAUUUCACUAUGAAGAUGUUUGAUUAAACUUAUGGACUUAGUGCCUUUAAACUGAUCAUCAGGGAGAAUCUUGAAAAAAUCAUUUGAAGGGCUGAUGUGAAGGAGCACUGUAAAUUUUUAUAACUUAGUAAUGAGUAUUCUUAGGCAGAUGUAAAAUUUUUUCCAAUUUAUUUUUAUUUAUGUAGCUUAUAAAAUUAACAUACCCUGUUUUACUUUAUGAUAAAGGAUUUUUUGUUUGCUGAAUUUAAAAUUAUAUAUUAGUGAUACCAUCAGAGGGCAGUGAUGUUCUAUUGUAUAUUAAAUUCAGCUCUGUAAGGAUCUUUGUAGUAAUUGAAUGAGUUAAACUAAUAAUCUGGAUGGGUUAUAAUGAGUAGUAAUAUAUUUGUCCAUAUUUCAUAAGUAGUGUUAAUCUUGUGUACUUAUUAGAGAACGAUCAUAAGAUUUAUACAGAUGUGAAACUGCGAAGGCAAGUAUGAAUGUAUGAAAAAAACAUGUAGGUACUGUACUUACAAAAGGUCUACUUCAGAUAUAAAAAUAUUAGGUAAUUCUAUACAAUGCAUAGUCAUAAACCUUAACAUUUUUGUUCAUUAGAAACAUGAAUUUUAUAGCAUUUUUUGUUUCUCCUAUAUAAUACACUGAAAUAAAAGAAUUUGUGUUAGCUAUUAAGGCUGAUAGCUCUUUUAAAUGGCAAGGCCACAUGUUGAGCCCUAAAUUAAAAUUUGCAGAUAUUAAGUGCUAAUAGAAAUUUUAAGUUAAAUCGACCAAGUUCACUUGCUUUACACAAAGGAAACUGAGCCACUAUCUUCAUCUACCCCUCCAACAAAAAUUAUGUUAUACUGCAGUGUAUUGUACAUGUUAAUUUUUAAAAGUUUGAACUAUUAUAUAAUACAGGUCUCUUGACUUCUCAUGGAAAAAUUAUUUUUUCUAUUAUGGUGUGAAAUAUUGUGUGAAUAUCUAGGCAAAACAUAACAAUUUGGCUCAAUUUUCUUCUUUAGAGGAUUCGUGCUGUUUUUGUUCAUAAAGGGUAGUGAAAUCAUUGAACUAUAUUUUAGAAUGAAAAUUUUUGAUUUUAUUAAAAUGAUUUUUUCAAGGCAGAAAGUAAAAGGAAUGAUUGAUAGCGGAGUGCAUAUAGAGCUAGAGCAUAUCAUCCUUGAACUCUGCAAAUCCUUUCUUCCAUUUUAAUAUAGCAAGAACAAUUUUGUCUUUACUACAUCUUAAAGAAUUAGAACUUGGGUUGGUGUAAGUGACUUACUUCCAGGGAAUCAUGCCCUAUUUCUACCAGCAGGUCAUACCCAAAUGUCACACUAUCUAUUGUUAACCAUGAAUGAUAUUCAGAUCUAUUACUUUUCGUGAAAAGUGGAACAUGUUACUUCCAACCAUGGCCUGUCACCGUGAGUGUGAUCAGCUUUCUCCAAAACCACAUGGGUCGCAGGAGCUAAGGGGUGGUACCCAAAUGUUAGGAACAGUGUUAGGAAAGGGCAAGGGAAAAGAAGUGACUGGAUGUCUUAUGAGAAACCGGUAAAUGACUAAAAAAAAAAGCAAAUGACUAAAAACAUGACUAAAAAAUUAUAUAUAUAUAUAAUAUAUAUAUUAUAUAUGUGUGUAUAUAUAUACACAUAAUAUCUGCAAAUUCUAAUUUAUAUAUGUGUGUGUAUAUACACACACACACAUGCACAUACACACAUACGUCCAGACAUCUCCCUCAUAAAAUAACCAUCAGUUUCUAUGAAAACCUUAAGUGGAAGCCAAUUUCCCAUAGUAAAUAAUUUAGGAGAAAAUUAUAAUGCUUAAAAUGUUGCUCAAACCCCUGACCUAUUACUAAACUAUAAUUGGAACAGUAAAAUGCAUAUAUGUAACUAUCAUAUCAUGAUUUAAAAUUGCUUAAACCAUUGCUGCUUAAUACUAAUCAAACUUAACGGCUGCUAACAAAAGUUGUGAAUUAUUACACGGCCUCUUUGUAACGUGCUGCAUGUUUUUUAAAACAUCUCUGUGUUUCUGUUUGUUCCACUGCUGGUAUUUGGAAUGUAAUUUAACAGUUCUCACACAUGGUUUGGUUAUAAAUUCUGUAUUGCCUUUUAGGGAUAUAAAUAUACAUUUUUUUCUAUGUAAAAAUUAGCUUUAGCUGUCUCUUUAACAAAAUUUUAUCUUUACUACAUCCUAAAUACUUAGAACCUGAGUUGGUGGUUAGGGAAACCUCAGGAACAUUUUAAUCACAUUGGGAUUCAGAAGAGCAACAGAACCAAAGGUUGUUUGGUGUGUUCAUACAAUCCCUGGAUUUAUAGGUGGAUUUUCUAUAAAGGAAAAAUGAUGUAAUUAGUAUCCUGUUUUUUCCUAAAGAAAUAAUACUAUCAUAAAAAUUCUGUCUAUCCUUUGUACCCCAGGAAAAUGGACAUGAACUUUGAAUUUUCCCUUUCUCCAAAUGUUUGACUUUUUAUUUUCACUGAUAAGCAUUAUGCUAUGUUCUUAGAAGACAAAAGCAGCUCUUGCCAGUUUUGAAUAAUUUCUGCAUGAAUAGACCAGUAAGAGGUAAGUAGCCAUGACUGCCUAUAUGUGUUGAGACAUAAGGUAUAUUUCUUUAACAUCUCCAAGCAAGCAUUUCAAAUUCUCUUAACUACUAAACAUGCUCUAAGCUAAUUCAAAUAUAGUAUUGUGGCUUUUUUCUUCAAUUUUCUCAAAAGCUACAGACACAAGGCAUUUGUAUGUAUAACAGACUUUGAUGAAGUUUUGGUUCCAGUAACUCAAAACACUAAGUUUCCCAUUUGAUAUGGCUUUUUAUUGUUCUAGUCUCCCUCUUCUAGUUAUGCUUCAUCUUGCAAAUAUUGACUUUGAAUGUGAUAACUAUUGCCUACAAAUUAAGUAUUCAUACAUUACUCCUGUGGAUAUCAUACUUUUUUGUUAUUAUAUCCUGAAUUGCAUUGGCUUUUUUUGGUUUUGUUUUGUUUUUUGAGAUGGAGUUUCACUCUUGUUGCCCAGGUUGGAGUGCAAUGGCACAAUCUCAGCUCACCGCAACCUCUGCCUCCCAGGUUCAAGUGAUUCUCCUGCCUCAGCCUCCCUAGUAGCUGGGAUUGCAGGCAUGUGCCACCACGCCUGACUAAUUUUGUGUUUUUAGUAGAGACAGGGUUUCUCCACGUUGGUCAGGCUGGUCUCGAACUCCUGACCUCAGGUGAUCCCUGCCGCCUUGGCCUCCCAAAGUGCUGGGAUUACAGGCAUGAGCCACCGCGCCCGGCCUGCAUUGGCUAUAUUUAUAAUACCAAAUUUGUGUUGAGUUUUGAGUUAAUGUCUUCUAGUUAUCAAAACAGGUUUGAUCCAUUCUUUGCAAGUACCUCUAACUUAUCUCAAGUGGAACUAAUUAGUUUUGCACACAGAUUGGUGCUCUCUAGGCUAUUUCCCUGAAAUUUAUCUUGUUACAUAAGUCAGAUAUCAAGGAGUUAUGCUAAACUCCUUUUCCUAUCAAACUCCUAAAAUGCCCUUUUCUCUGUCUAUAUUUCUUAGACAUAGUUACAUUAUAAAUGUAACAGAUAUAUUUAAAGUAGGUUAAUACCAAGUGUCUCAGGUAGAAAAUUCUCAGAGGUUCCACAAAAACUUCUGGAACUAAUAAAUGACUUUAGUAAUCUUGCAGAAUGAAAAGUAUAUGAAAGUCAAUUCUAUGUUUAUAUGCAAGCAAUGAAAAAUCUGUAAUUGAAAGUGGGAAAAUUUAAAUUACAAUAUCAACAAAUAAAAUAUUUAGGAAAAAUAAAACUGUAGACAUUAAAAAUGACAAAACAUUGCCAAUAAAUUAAGAUCUAAAUGAA